GAGCCCAGCUGCUGGAGCCCCGAGCAGCGGCAUGGAGUCCGUGGCCCUGUACAGCUUUCAGGCUACAGAGAGCGACGAGCUGGCCUUCAACAAGGGAGACACACUCAAGAUCCUGAACAUGGAGGAUGACCAGAACUGGUACAAGGCCGAGCUCCGGGGUGUCGAGGGAUUUAUUCCCAAGAACUACAUCCGCGUCAAGCCCCAUCCGUGGUACUCGGGCAGGAUUUCCCGGCAGCUGGCCGAAGAGAUUCUGAUGAAGCGGAACCAUCUGGGAGCCUUCCUGAUCCGGGAGAGUGAGAGCUCCCCAGGGGAGUUCUCUGUGUCUGUGAAGCUGGAGUGCAGCGGCGUGAUCAUGGCUCACUGCAGCCUCAAACUCCUGGGCUCAAGCGAUCCUCCCACCUCAGCCUCCCAAGUCUUUGGGAUUAUAGGCGUGAGCCACCGUGCUGGCUUGCCUUUGGUUCUCUGAACUACUCCAGUUCUUUCCACUAAAUCCACCCCCCUCUUUUUUCCCCUUUGGUUAAUCAGAAUCCAUAUCUUUUGCUCCAGAUCAAAGAACCCUACCCGAUGAUCCCUUCUCCAUUCACAAAAUCAAUAACAUACUCAAAAUCAAUAAACAGCUGACCGAGCACAGUGGCUCACGCCUGUAAUCCCAGCACUUUCGGAGGCAGAGGUGGGCGGAUCACAAGGUCAGGAGUUCGAGUCCAGACUGACCAACAUGGUGAAACCCCGUCUCUACUUAAAAAAUACAAAAAUUAGCUGGGCGUGGUGGUGUGCACCUGUAAUCCCAGCUACUUGGGAGGCUGAGGCAGGAGAAUGGCUUGAACCCGGGAGCCCGAGAUUGCAGUGAGCUGAUAUCAUGCCACUGUACUCCAGCCUGGGUGACAGAACGAGACUCCAUCUCAAAAAAAAAAAAAAAAAAAAAAAAAAAGAAUGUGGCCGGGCGCGGUGGCUCACGCCUGUAAUCCCAGCACUUUGGGAGGCCGAGGCAGGUGGAUCACCAGGUCAGGAGUUCGAGACCAGCCUGGCCAAUUUGGUGAAACCCCGUCUCUACUAAAAAAUACAAAAAUUAGCCAGGCAUGGUGAUGGGCGCCUGUCCCAGGCUGUUUUUAUGUUAUGUGGGGAUGAGGCACUGACCCUGUGGGCCGGGAUCUCUCUGGGGACGCUUCCCUUGCUUUUUGUCUACACUCCUUAAGGCAAACUACUUGGGAGGCUGAGGCAGGAGAAUCACUUAAACCCGGGAGGCGGAGGUUGCAGUGAGCUGAGAUCGCGCCACUGCACUCCAGCCUGGGCGACAGAGCAAGAAUCCAUCUCAAAAAAAAAAAAAAAAAGUAACAAGACUCUUAACAGCUGUGGAGAUCUGUGCCUAUUCUGAGUGCUUCUCCACUACUUCCUGAUACUGAUUUAGCUCUGUGUAUAUAUUUGUUGAAGUAAUGCUUAGAUCUUAGUUGUAUUCAUCCAGUGCCCUCCCAAUCAUGUUUUGUGUGGAAUAGCAAAUCACUUUCUGCUUGUAUUCCAAAAAUGUUGCAGAAAGACUUGCCACCCUGCUGGGGACUGUCCCUGCCCCCUGACCACUUCUGGCCUGCCUUACACUCGAUUAUUUUGGGCAAAAAGUGCAAAUCAAGACUGAGAUGUCAGGCCAGGUGCAGUGGCUCAUGCCUGUAAUCCCAACACUUUGGGAGCCGAUGGAUCACUCAAGCCCAGGAGUUCAAGACCAGUCUGAGUAACAUGGCGAAAAAAACCUGUCUUUACAAAAAGUAAAAUAAUUAGUGAGGCGUGAUGGCAUGCGCACACCUGUAGUCUCAGCUUCUCGGGAUAGUCACAGCUACUUGGGAGGCUGAGGUGGGAGGAUCACCUGAGGCCAGGGACACAGGUACAUCAAGGCUGCAGUGGGCUGUGAUCACACCACUGCACUCCAGCCUGAGUAACAGAGUAAUACCCUGUUUCAAAAAAAAAAAAAAAGAAAGAAAGAAAGAACAAACAAAGAAAAAAAACAAAAAGGAAAAGGAAAAAGAAAGAGAGAGAGAGAGAGAGAGAUAAUCCAGGACUUUUUUUGAAGGGAGAGGGAAACAGGACUGUCUGACACGCGGGAAAAUUGCUUGAAUUCUCCAGCCUUCCCAUUUGGAUGCUUUUCUCUUUGCGUGAACACAGCCAUAAGCUGGCUCGUUAUAGAGGCAUAGGCAGUGGUUGAAAAUACAGGUCCUAGCAACAAGGAAGUCUGGGUUUGAAUCCAGACUCAGCCACUUUCCAGCUGUGUGACCUGGGAGAAGUCACUGUUCCUCUCUGAGCCUGGAGCUACCUGCAUCACUACCCUGAACUGAUGAAUGGAAAGCACUUGGUACAAAAUCCAGCACAUACUUGGCACACAUAACUCACAGCUCGGUGUAAUUAGAAGAAUGCCAGGAGGACUGGCCUGCACGCUGGAAGGGGCUCUAGACAAGGCUGACCAUCAGGAUCCACUGGUUGGUCCAGAGAUCUCGGAACAGACUGGUUCUCCCCGCCGCUUCUGCCUCCCACUCACCUCCACCCGUUCAUGCAACUGUAGUUUUCUUAGCCCCUGAAACCGGGUUGGGGCUGCCGCAGGGGCCAUCAGGCUGUGAGGGAGGCUGACGCGGACACAGUAGGUAAGAGGCCAAGAUGUACAGUCCUGAAAGAGGGCAGGAGGCUGGUGACUCAGUGGGUGAGAAAAUGCAAAGGCUGGGGCUAUCUUAGCCCAGAAAAGGACAAAUUUUUUUUCCCCAAAUUAUUUUCCUUCUUUUGUCUCUUUCUCCCCUCCCUCUCUCGCUCCUUCCUGCUUUUCUUCCUUUCCCUCCGUUACUUUCUUUAAUCCAAAGGAAAUUUAAGUGGAGGACAUAAAAGCAUAUGCUGUUAUUAAUUUUUGCAAAUGUCCUUAACUGAGAGGCACUGAGCAGAAAGAAGAACACAAUUGCAUCUCCAUUAUCUUCAUCUGGGCCACCAGAUACCAGCCACCCACUCUCUCAGACAAUGGCAGAAAGGACAAGCCAGCCCCCAGGGACCCGGCCCUGCCAGCUUACCUGUUGGCACACCUCCCCUGAGCACUGCAGCCUCACCAACUGUCUGGGGUCCCUGAGACUGCCUGCUCACACUCACCUCUGAGCCUUCCUGUCUGCUGUUCCCUCUGCCUGGAACAUCCUCUCCACUCCCCCUUAGACCCCCUCUAGCAGCUGUCCUGGCUGACUGCUAAUUGGCUUUAGGAUUCAGGGAGGCAUCCUGCCUUGGGUGCCUUCUUUGAUGGCCACAGAUCAAGUUAGGGGUCUUCUCUGGCUGCUUAUCCUCAUAGCACCUGCUCCCGGAUGUGACAGACAGCUUCAGUUUUGUCACCCUGUGGUCCAGCAGCUUUCUGAGGGAGGGCUGGGACCAGCUCUCAUUUACCUGUGUCUCUCACCCCUGCAAGGUUCUGGCCACAGCAAGCAAUGCCUAAGCACAUAUUUGUGGAGUAAAGGUAUAAAAGACAAGGCAUCCCAGAUGGGCGUGGUGGCUCAAUCCUAGCACUUGGAGAGUCUGAGACGGGAGGAUCACUUGAGGGCAAGAGUUUCAGACCAGCCUGGGCAACCCAGUGAGACCCCAUCUCUACAAAAAAAACAUAUUUUUGUUUGUUUGUUUGUUUGUUUGUUGUUUUUUAAUUAGCCAGGCGUAUUGGUGUGCACCUGUAAUCUCAGCUACUUGAGAGGCUGAGGUGGGAGGAUCUGUUAAGCCCAGGAAGUUGAGGCUGCAGUGAGUUAUCAUCCCACCACUGCACUUCAGCCUGGGCAAUGGAGCAACACCCUGUCUCAAAAAAAAAAAAAAAAAAAAGGCAAGACAUCAAGACAUCCCUGGAGGAAGCCACUCUGUAGACCACAGGCUAACAGAGCAUGGUUGAGCAGGGAGGAGUUGGGAGCUGCACCCAGCACCUCACACAAUGUUAUCAUGGAGCUGGGGACAGAGCAGGUUCCAGAGCUGGGUUUGAGUCCCAGCUCCUCCGAUGAUGAUAUGACACCCCAGACAUGUGCAGGGAUGUCCUCUAAGCCUCAGCUUCCUCACUGCAAUUUGGGGCUCUGUCUCUUUCUGGCAGGGAGUUAUUGGGAAGACCAAAUGAGAUCAUGUCCCCCUCCCAAACCCUGCAAGGCCUUUGCGUCACAGUUAGAAUGAAGUCUACAUAUAGCCCUGUCCACUCGCAGCCUGCCUCCCUUCCCCAUUCGCACCCUUACACACGGAGCCCCCUCCAACCUCCCCCCCACACACACUGAGCCCUGUGCUCUUUCCUCUGCCCAAAUGGCCCUUCCCUCAGACAUCUAGAUGUCCAUCCUCCUUCCCUCAGUCUGCCUCUCGGAGCAGUCUUCCCGACCACUACAACGAUGCCUCCCCAACCCCGGCCUGCGUCACUCCCCACGCCCACCCUGCUUUGCAGCAUCGCUCCCUGGCUGACAUUACAUCAUGCAUUUAUUUCUUUGCUUAUUGUCUCCCUCCCCUCCAUGAGGGCAGGAACCUUCAUCUGUCUUGUUGACAGUAGCAUCCCUAGAACCUAGCUCAGGCCUGACUCACAGUGUGUGCUCAGUCCACAUUUGGGAAACCAAUGGAGAGAUGAAUGGCACAGAGAUGCGCUCAGGAACCCAGUUCCCUGACCUCCCAUCCAGGCUGCACCCCUCAGGAGUCUAGGUUCCUGCUGAUUGGUAGAGUUCAGGACCCAGGGCUGGAAAGUGUCCACCCACAGGGCAGAUGGGCCAAGGCCACGUGCUCAAGGUGUGCAGGGCUAGGAGAGGGGGUCAGCCCCAGCUCCCAUAUGAGGGGCAUGUGCCUCGCCUUGCCCCUGCUUUGGCUAGAGGGUACCCUGUUCACCAGAGAUGAGCCUAGGCUCUCCCCGGGCCUGGCUCUGGCUUUACCCCAGAGCCCUCCAACUCGCAGACCUCCAGGCAAGGAGGGCUGGGGACCCACCCGUACCAGCCAUUUGCCUUUUCUCCAGUAACAGAGCCCAGAGGGGUCCCUGCCUGGGCCCAAAAUCACACAGCAGAUUGGGGUAGAGCCGGAGAGGACCCGAGACUCCUGUGCCAGCCUGGGCAUCCCCUCCACUGCCAGGGAAGGACUGCAUCCAAGUCGCAUCCGUACCCAGGCCGAGGUGUCCGAGGCCCAGGCUGAAAUCCGGUUGCUGCUGCAGAGACCAAGUUUCCAAGGCCUUGUCAAGUGGGCUGUGCCAGACGAUCCCCAGGCCUGUCAUUGGCUGCUCUUCGGCUCGGACACACCAAACCUCACCAAGCACUUCCAUUUCUGAGGGAAUAGAGGUUGUGGCUUCCGUCAAGCACCCAUUUACCCCACCCUCCUCCUCCUCUUCCUGCAAACUUGAGUCACAGCUGCCCUGCUGGGCUCAGGCCCCAGGGAUGUCUGAGUCAGCCUGGCUGGGGUUCCAGUCCUGACACCGCCCUUACCAGCUGGGAGACUCCGGGAACCUCCAACCCUGCUGAGCCUCCACUUCGACAUCCGUGAAACAGCCAUGAAUAAGCAGGUCUCAAAGGUCGACUCCUGUAUGCAGGGACACAGCAUGCAGUAGGUGCCCAAUCAUAACAGCAGCACCCACCUGGAGCCCCUUAUAGCAGCCCUUCUCCUCUGCACUUCCACAUGGCAUCUCAUUUAACCUUCACCACAACCCAACUAGGAAGGCACCAUCAUUAUCCCAUUUUACUGAUGAAGAAACUGAGGCCCAGGAAGGUGAAUUUACCAGCCAGCUCACAAAUGGACUAGUAGAUGGCAGUUUGUGGAUUGGAGCCCAGAGGCUGUGCUCCUGCCCACACCCUCUCAAAUGAGGGCUAUAAAAUAACACUCUAAGAGCUCUUCCUA